ACACUCCACACCCUCAUUUUCCAGCAGUGAGGGUAGACUAUUAAGGCUCUCAUGUCAUCAAGGAUCGAGGCAAUGGGUUAAUGGAGACUCUAGACAUUUGUUUCCUCACCAGUGAAAAUUAAAUGAAGACCCAGGAAUCACUACAGCUAUAGGGAUGAGAAGGACAUUUCAGCAGCUAGAGUGUGGUGAAAUAUGGCAGGCACACAGGCCUGAGACUGGAGUACGGCUUCCUACUUCUUCCUCCGCAAACUAAAGACAGCGAGCCCCAGGGUGCUAAUCCAACUGAGCUGCCACUCCAACUACAAUUAGCGAAGCUGAACAAGAAAGGAGAGAUGGAAAACCUGCCCCUAAAUGAGGUUUCCUAACCUCAUGUGUUUUCCAGUGAAGCGAAUUACAAAGGCAUUAUUUACUCAGGAGAAAAAAGUAUAGGAAACUAAAGAAAAUACUGAAGAUAAUCUCAAAUGGUGACAAUCUUUUUCAAUCUCAUCUACACUUCAAUUUUGGAAUAGUCUAUAAUAUUUGAGAAUUAACAGAAAUAUUGCAAGAUAAAAGCUAGCAACUGUUAUGUAAAAGUAUCCAUUUUCCAUGGAUUCCCGCUAAAAGACUAACAGUUACUAAAUCAUCCCCACAAGCCAACUGCUUUUAAAAAGACCUCUACUACAACACAAGAUGGUGCCACUAGCAUAUUAUGGUCAACACUUUGUGCCAUUAGACUACUUCUACCAACUGUCCUCAGCCAAUACAUUAACACAUCAACAUACAGGUGAAAAACUAAAUCAAUUCAAUAACCAACCUAUGGCCAAAGUGCAAUCCCAUAGCAAUCACUUUGCAGUACCUCCACUGGGCUCCAAUAAGAAGGUCCAGAGAUGCUCAGUAUUGCCUUCUCCCAAAUCUCAGGACAAAAUUUCACAGAGCUUCUGUGAUAGGUUUCUGAAUUCACCAUUGUUCCAUGCCAAGCAUCAGAACACACCUUCAAUAGGCCUCCACUGGAGAAGUUCAUUGUGGCCUGCUCAAAGAGCCCUGAACUCUCAUUUGUUGCACUCCAAAGCUCAAACAACGUCUUCAUCUGACCUCAACAUGACAUCAUCACUGGAGCUCAAUCAAGCAGCCCUGAGUUUACAAUUACCCUUCUGUAAACCUCAAACAACAUCUUCAAGCCUAGAUGUUUGCUGGAGAUCACUUUCAUUGAAGUCUCAUCAAAGAGUCUCAAGUUCAUCAUUAUUUCGCCUCCAAAAUCAAGAAAUACCUUCCAUAAACAUCAUUUGGACAUCAUCUUCCUUGGGACCCAAACGAAAAGCCCUUAGCUCGACAUUGCUUCAAUCCAAACCUCAGAAAACAUCCUCAUUGGACUACCUUUGGACAUCUUCAUUGCAGCGCAAUCAAAGAUCUUUGAGUUCACCAUCACUCAACACAAAACUUCAAACAAGUGACUUAUUUUGGACAUCACCUUCUUUCAAACCCAAUCAAAUUGCUCUUACCUCUCCAUUACUUGACUCUAGGCUUCAGAAAACACCUAUAUUGAACUCUAACCCCACUAUUGGAGGCUUACCAGUGUCCCAUUCAAAAGCAAGGCAAUCAGCAUCAUCAUAUUUUGUCCACCCAUCUGAGAAUUUACCAUUGUUUCAGCUCAAUUCUCAGUCAAUGUUUAUGCUUGAUUGUAACUUCCAGACCACGAAUUCACCUGUCUGUCACUCCAAGUUUCAGAAUACCACUUCACCAAAUGGCAAACACAGAGUCACACAUCUACCAUCACCCCAUCCAAAAACAAACAUCUCAGGUCAAUUAUUAUCAAGCUCCAAACACUGCACCAGGAACACAGCUGCUUCAACAUUAGGUUUCAGACUCCAGAGUAAAAGCAGCUUUCAGUUUUCUCCAAAGACAGAAUCAAAUAAAGAAAUUCCUUGGACUUUAAAGUAUAGUCAGCCCUGCAUUGUUAAAGGUGGAACUGUCCCUGAUGAUGUGGUAAAUAAAAUUGUCAAUUCUAUCUCAAAUACCAGAAUACAGAGGGAUCUCUGUAGGCAGAUUUUGUUUAGAAGGAUGAGGGGAAGGCCAAAUCCUCAUCCUGGUCCUCGCUUGUCAUCAAAUUAUGUGGUUUGCUUAGCUUGUGCUUCCUGCCUAAAAUCUCCAUGUAACCAUCUUAGAGGAAAGAAAAAUCCUCAUUGUGCAACACUUUCUGUCAUACCAACACCUGAGGCCAAUUCUGAGGGCAAAAUAGAAGUGAAAUUAGUUCUUAUCCUUUCUCUACCAGAGACUUUCUCAUCUUGUCUCCCAUUCCCUAUGAAAGAAAACCAGCCUAAUGAAGUCCCUGAAGACAACCUUGAAGGAGUAGAGAAGAUACAGCAGUUUUUCCCCACAUCUGAACGGGAUAUCCAGGGACUUAAUAUGAAGCAAAUAUGGUGGGCGGUAGCCCCCGAAAACAAAGUUAUAGGCCAACAGCCCCAGGCUAUUGACUGGCUGUUUUAUGUUAAAAAAAAUAAUUCUCAGCCACAAUCCCUGCUCCCAUCCACCUCCUCCUCCACUUCCUCCUCCUCCACCACCUCCUCCUCCUCCUCUGUUGCCUCUGCCUCUUCUGACUCCUCUUCUUCAUCUUCUUCCUCCUCUUCCUUUUCCAUCUCAUCCUCUUCCUCUCCUUCCAAAGAGUUUAUGACCCUCACUCUCUCACGUCCUGUAUUCCGUAAGGUACUUAGCUACCAUCGGUUGCCUGCAGGGGUCUCCUGGCUUGAGUUUAUAUAUAGCAAAGAUUACCAGCUGCAUCCCAGAAAACCAAAUCGAAGCCAAUCAUCAUCUCUUAAAACAAAGCCUGUGAGGAACAACAAUACAGUAAAAUGGAGAAAGGGAGCAAACACACUGUUCAAAUUUUUCCGGACAAAAUGAGAAAUUGUGAUUAAAUUAAUCUUUAGUCUGUU